AGACCUGGGAUCAAACAGAAAGGAAUGUCUGGGUUAAGAUAAGAGGCUGUAGCGACCAAGGUUUUAUCAUGCAGAUGAAGCUUUUAGCUAGCAGGCUUCAGAGAGAAUAGGUUGCAAAAUGUUUCUUAUUAGACUUAAAGUCUGUGUUGAUGUUAAUGCCAGAGAGGUAUAACGAGGCAUGUUUGACCCCCACUUCCCAUCAUGCCCUGAAACAGUCUCUCAGGUUAAAUUUUAAGGGCGCUGACUGAGGAGGAAGUCCAUUCAGAUGGUUGGGGGGCCUUAGAAUUUUAUUUUUGGUUUAUACUCCUUUAACUCUGUUCCUUCUGAUGGGAGGGAUGGCAUCUUAGUUCCUGGAAAUGAAAGAUGAAAACCAUAACCCCAAGUUUUGACGUAAGGUUUACCGAGGUAAUUUAAUGGGGCUAAGAUGUAGAAAAGGAAGAAGAACUCUUUAAAGUAAAUUAUUCUGGCUGGGUGUGGUGGCUCAUGCCUGUAAUCCUAGCACUUUGGGAGGCCAAGGUGGGAGGACUGCUUGAGUCCAGGACUUCAAGACCAACCUGGGCAACAUAGCAAGACCCUGCCUCUAUUAUUAAUUUAAAAAAGAAGAAAUAAAGCAAAUUGUUCUAAGUCAGGUUGGAAUGAAUCAUUCUAAAGCUCUGCUCAUGGAAAUCACCCCAGUUGGCAAACCCUCUUGCCUGGGAGGCCAACAUAAUAGGCACUGCCUUGACUGUCUCCAAGAAGAAAGGUGAUCCAAUCUCAACAGGCAUGCUUUCCUAAAACUGGACAAGAAGAAUAAAUGGUUUUUGCUGGACAGGAAGAAUUACAGCUGCCUGCUGAAGAUGAAGUCUUACUACAGAAAUUAAGAGAGGAAUCAAGAGCUGUCUUUCUACAAAGAAAAAGCAGAGAACUGUUAGAUAAUGAAGAAUUACAGAACUUAUGGUUUUUGCUGGACAAACACCAGACACCACCUAUGAUUGGAGAGGAAGCGAUGAUCAAUUACGAAAACUUUUUGAAGGUUGGUGAAAAGGCUGGAGCAAAGUGCAAGCAAUUUUUCACAGCAAAAGUCUUUGCUAAACUCCUUCAUACAGAUUCAUAUGGAAGAAUUUCCAUCAUGCAGUUCUUUAAUUAUGUCAUGAGAAAAGUUUGGCUUCAUCAAACAAGAAUAGGACUCAGUUUAUAUGAUGUCGCUGGGCAGGGGUACCUUCGGGAAUCUGAUUUAGAAAACUACAUAUUGGAACUUAUCCCUACGUUGCCACAAUUAGAUGGUCUGGAAAAAUCUUUCUACUCCUUUUAUGUUUGUACAGCAGUUAGGAAGUUCUUCUUCUUUUUAGAUCCUUUAAGAACAGGAAAGAUAAAAAUUCAAGAUAUUUUAGCAUGCAGCUUCCUAGAUGAUUUAUUGGAGCUAAGGGAUGAGGAACUGUCCAAGGAGAGUCAAGAAACAAAUUGGUUUUCUGCUCCUUCUGCCCUAAGAGUUUAUGGCCAGUACUUGAAUCUUGAUAAAGAUCACAAUGGCAUGCUCAGUAAAGAAGAACUCUCACGCUAUGGAACAGCUACCAUGACCAAUGUCUUCUUAGACCGUGUUUUCCAGGAGUGUCUCACUUAUGAUGGAGAAAUGGACUAUAAGACCUACUUGGACUUUGUCCUUGCAUUAGAAAACAGAAAGGAACCUGCAGCUCUACAAUAUAUUUUCAAACUGCUUGAUAUUGAGAACAAAGGAUACCUGAAUGUCUUUUCACUUAAUUAUUUCUUUAGGGCCAUACAGGAACUAAUGAAAAUCCAUGGACAAGAUCCUGUUUCAUUUCAAGAUGUCAAGGAUGAAAUCUUUGACAUGGUAAAACCAAAGGAUCCUUUGAAAAUCUCUCUUCAGGAUUUAAUCAACAGUAAUCAAGGAGACACAGUAACCACCAUUCUAAUCGAUUUGAAUGGCUUCUGGACUUACGAGAACAGAGAGGCUCUUGUUGCAAAUGACAGUGAAAACUCUGCAGACCUUGAUGAUACAUGAUCUCUGAAAGACUAGACUGUCUUAUAUUAUGAGAUACUUGAAUGCUGCAUGUAAAGCCUUUAAAGCAAAAUCCUCAGAAAUGGUCUAAAUAAAACACUUGAUAUGCCUAGAGAACACA